GCUGCUGGCGGAACCUGCAGGAGCUAGCGGGAUUCGGGGGCGCUAAAGUCGCAGGGGCAGGGCGGGAAGGAAGAUCCGGCGCGGGGCACAGGAUCCGGAGCUGGAGCCCCCAGAGGCCUCACGACAGGACUAGUGCCUUGGUAAGAAGAGGAAAAGGCCAGAGCUCCCUCCCUACCCUGUGUGGACCCAGCAGGAAGGAAUUCUGUCUGCAAGAGAGAGCCCUCACCUGGAACCAAAUCAGCCAGGACCCUGAUGUUGGAUUUACCAGCCUCCAGCACCGUGAGACAGAAACGUCUGCUGUUUCAGCCACCCAGAAUUUUCCCACUGUAAAAAACCGAGCAAGUCUGGAUAAGUGAGGCUGGCUCCAUGUAUCCAGAAUCAACGACGGGCUCCCCGGCUCGGCUCUCGCUGCGGCAGACGGGCUCCCCCGGGAUGAUCUACAGUACUCGGUAUGGGAGUCCCAAAAGACAGCUCCAGUUUUACAGGAACCUGGGCAAGUCUGGCCUGCGGGUCUCCUGCCUGGGACUUGGAACAUGGGUGACCUUCGGAGGCCAGAUCACCGAUGAGAUGGCAGAGCAGCUCAUGACCUUGGCCUAUGAUAAUGGCAUCAACCUCUUCGAUACAGCAGAAGUCUACGCAGCCGGCAAGGCUGAAGUGGUACUGGGAAACAUCAUUAAGAAGAAAGGAUGGAGGCGGUCCAGCCUCGUCAUCACCACCAAGAUCUUCUGGGGCGGAAAGGCGGAGACGGAGCGGGGCCUGUCCAGGAAGCACAUAAUCGAAGGUCUGAAAGCUUCCCUGGAGCGACUGCAGCUGGAGUACGUGGAUGUGGUGUUUGCCAACCGCCCGGACCCCAACACCCCGAUGGAAGAGACCGUCCGCGCCAUGACCCACGUCAUCAACCAGGGGAUGGCCAUGUACUGGGGCACGUCACGCUGGAGCUCCAUGGAGAUCAUGGAGGCCUACUCCGUGGCCCGGCAGUUCAACCUGACCCCGCCCAUCUGCGAGCAGGCUGAGUACCACAUGUUCCAGCGUGAGAAAGUGGAGGUGCAGCUGCCGGAGCUGUUCCACAAGAUAGGAGUGGGCGCCAUGACCUGGUCCCCUCUGGCCUGUGGCAUUGUUUCUGGCAAGUACGACAGUGGCAUCCCACCCUACUCAAGAGCCUCCUUGAAGGGCUACCAGUGGCUGAAGGACAAGAUCCUCAGUGAGGAGGGCCGGCGCCAGCAAGCCAAGCUGAAGGAGCUGCAGGCCAUCGCCGAGCGCCUGGGCUGCACCCUGCCCCAGCUGGCCAUAGCCUGGUGCCUGAGGAAUGAGGGAGUCAGCUCCGUGCUCCUGGGGGCCUCCAAUGCGGACCAGCUCAUGGAGAACAUUGGGGCAAUACAGGUAAGAGUGAGAGGCCCUGCUGGGCAGAGGGCCCAUCCCAGCCCGAGCCCCGUCCAGUGCAUCCUCCCAGGCUCGUCCUGCGUGCCAGGCUCUGUUCUAGGCACUCAGGAUGCGCCCGUGAACCAUCAGAGUUGUGCUCCUGGAGAGCUUGCUUUCCAGCAGGAACAGACAUGAACACUAACUGCACGAAACAAGGAGGUCCUUCCGAAACUGUCAUCUUCCAUUAUCCACGAGAUUGAUAGUAUUUUGGGCAAUAAACCCUACAGCAAAAAGGACUACAGAUCCUAAGCCGCCCCCGCCCGCCUGCUCGGACAGUUUCCGUUCCCUCCUAGUCUCUGUUCGCUCGCUUAAGCUGUUUUGAAGCCAAGUGAAGAGUGUGGUUUGCAUCCAAGAGAAAACACCACACUGUGAUGUCAUCGGGAAAUGAUCUCCCAAGUCGCUGCCAGACACCACCCACUGCUUCGCCGGACAAUGUCGAAGUCCAGUCUGUGCCGGGGAAGGCACUGGUUAGGAAGGAUGUUCAAACGGUCCCACCCAAGCCUGUCACCUCUGCUCAUCCUCCAAGACCACCCAGCUUUCUCCCAGCCACAGCCAAGAUUCCCAAAGUCAAGGCCCAAAGAUUUCCAAGGUUCCCAAAGUCAAGGCCAGGCCAAGGCCUGGUUGGGUCCUUGGGGCGGGCAGGGCCAGCCUCUCCUCUGCUGAGAAUCCCCACUUGGUGUAGGGGGAGAGGGGAAAGGGGUCUGGCCCAUCGAGGGGCCCCUUCUGCCAGGGCCUUGGUUGCUGGGGCAGGGCCUCCCCACUGGGGGUCUUCCUCCACCUCCCACUUUCCAAGGGCUCCAGGAAUCUGGGGCCUGACCACAGAUUCCUCUCCCAUCCUUUUCUGCUCCAACCUGCCCCACUGGGUCCCGGCAGGGGCCAUGCCUACCAAGCUCGAGCUGGCCCUUGACCCCCACCCACCCCCACCCUUGCUGGCAGGGGCAGGGACCCCAGGGGGAUUGACUCUGCAGUUUGGGAGCCACAAAAAGCGUAGCGGUGUGAUUUCUAGCUCAGCCUCCCACCGUCUUCCUCCUACACACCAAUGAUGAGCCUCAUGCCAGUGAGGCCCGGAGCGCUUGGGAGGGGUCCCAGUGGGGCAGGCCCCUCUGUCUGGCCACCCCUCUGUCCUGGCCCCGGAAGGCCCUGUGGUCAUGUGCUCCUAGCUGCACGGUGGCUGCUGGCCACACCACGGCAAGUGGCAGCAGGGGCCGGCCCUGUGCACAAGGAUGCACUCCUCUCGGCCCCUGUAGACUUUCUCUAAAGCCGCCCGCCAGCCCAGGCCGCUGCUCUGCACCGAGCUGGUGGGCUUGGGUUUUGUGGAGCGCAUGCUUGGACCCUUUCAGUAAGGAAGGGUCUUUGGGGUUUUCUGUGCCCAUGACUUGGGGGCUGCACCCCCACAGCACCCCCACAAUGUAGGAAAAGACCUCAGGGAACCUCUCCCUGGAAAGACGGGCAGGGCUGGUUAGCCCCUCCCACUGCCUGACACCUGGGACAGGCUGGGCAGAGGGGAGAGAGGGCAGGACAGGCCAGAGUGACGCCCCCGUGCAGCUUGGGCCGGAGGGCAAGGGAUGCCAGUAAGUCUGCAGGUGCGGGGUGCCACCUACAGGCCCAGGCCUGUGUCCCAAGCAGUACCCAGGCUUUGCAGACCACGCGGGGCAGGGCUCCACUGAAGCCACCCCCACCCCUCGCCAGCUAGCUCCAUAGGGAAGCCUGUGUCUCCUGCCCCCAGGGCGCACCCUCAGUGCAGGCACCUCUGUUCCCGCUUUGCCCCUGGAGGAGCCACUAUUCCAGAAGGCUCCACCCUGCCGUCCUGCGGGAGCCUGCUGUCCAGUCCUGGCCGGGCCAAGGCCUGGGAAACUGUGAAAGUCAGAAAGGCCAGCGGGGAGAGGCUGGGGCGAGGGGAGGAGGGGGAUCAGCUUCUGCUAUUACCGACCCCCCUUCAUGCUGCCCCUGGCGCCUAGAACCCUUGCCCCUCCUCAUAGACCAAGUCCCGGGGGUCUCCACUCAGUCCUGCUGCCUGCUUCACCAGAAGCAGCCCUGUGAGUGUGGGGUGGGGAAGUCCCUUCCCAACGGAGGUCCCAGCCUAUGGCCCUGGGCCCAGGUGGGGGUCGCCUGCUUCCUUCCCGGACAGGGUCCUGCAGUGGCCAAUGGUGCCAGAGGGCAGGUGGCCCACCCUCGCCAUCAGGGAGGGUGGCUGGCCCCAUCCCCACUGCCACCCAGCCCCACCCACUGUUGGAAGAGGGACCAGCGCGAGGUGGUGCCCAGGGUGGGCACUGCUGCUUAAUGCGAGGCACACCUGGGGCAGCUGAGCCCCCAAAGGCUGCGGGUUUGCCAAACACAGAGAGGCCAGGCCCCAGUGUCAGGAUGCAGUCAGCCUCUGGCGCAGCUCUUUCCACGACCUGGUUCCUGGAUGUCCUGCUUGCUCCACACCCAUCUACAGGGAGGAUGUGAGGGGGCUCUGCCUCCUAGGGCCAGGUCCCCCCUCUCGGGAGGAGGUAUUGGGUAGGACCAUCCAAGAAAGGGCAGAAGACCAAGGGCAGUCGGGGUCUAGAAAGGAGGGCGCUGGCCCUGCUGGACGCUUCGGAGCCCCCACUGUUUCCCACUCAGCUUUGUGCUCAGAUCCCAGGUCCCAAGGAGUGACAGGGGCUUCCUCCCACCUUCUGUCCUUGUCCAGUCAUGUAAAUAAUGUGCUUUUUCUCUCCCCGAGUCUUUUUUUUUAAACCUACCGUGGUUCCUCAGCUAACUGCAUUCCCUACCCAGGCAGAGACUGUCCUAUGCCUCGAGCUUCCAAACGAGACUCAGACCGCGACACAGCCACCGUAUUUAUGGAAUGACAAAAUAAAUAAAGCCCAAACCCA